AUGCUUCCACUUAAGCAUUCCCAAAAAGCUCGAGCCCUUCUCACCAAACCACAGCCCUUUAAGCAAGGCUCCAUGACCCCAAACAGCAUUUCCAGCAACAUAUCACAACAGCAGGGCAUUCAGUCAGAAAGCUGCACACUGUCCUCUAAAGAAGGCAAAGAGCAGCAACAGGCACUGAGACCUCACCUCCGGGUGCCCCGAAAACUGGCUUUAGCCGAGGCCCUGCAUCUAGACACACGCUGUGUCCACCAGAGAAUUGCCUGGGCUGACAGACCUAAAGCUUCCGCAACCUCCUUAGGCUCCCUAGUCCACGCCGCUGCUCCCCGGGCUGAGCAGGGCUGGGACGCGCCGCACAGAACUCAGGGACCCCACCUCCCUGCGCAUCUCCAGGGCCACGCUGGCACCUGCAGGAGUGCGGACUGUCCGCGGAUCCCAGGCAGGGUUGGGUGGAGAUUCGCAGCCAACCCACAGGAGUUCUGCCCUCCUCCCAGGCUUCUGGCCAGUGGAGUUGGAGAAGGGUCCCCGUCCUCGAGCCUGGGACACGCUCCGGGGCUCACAGAGACACUGACCCACACGUCCCCGUGGUUCGUAGCUCUGGGGGCGCUCCACUCCCUAGGUAAUGCUCCCGACGGGGAUCCCAACCCCGACCGCGCGGCAAGCCCGGGGUGUGGGGAGAGCCCACUGACCUGGAGCCCAGAAGCGAGCGACGGGCCACUGGCCCACCGACCAACUGCCGGACCAAGCGCCCGACCAACCAGCGGACCGACCGCAGCGGCCGGGGCCGGCGCCCACGUGACGGGGCGGGGACCUGCGGAAGGCUCUUCCCGGAGCGCCGCGCCCCCACCCCGGGACCUGCCACAGGGACCACCCCCUUGGGCACCCGCUCCCUCUCGGGCACCGAAGAAGCCUGCUGGGACCCGUCCACCAGGGUUCCUGUUCCCGGGGGACCGGCCUGGUCAGCCCCGCCCCUUCGAACCUGCCUCGUCCCCACCCCCUGGGCCGCGCGUCCGGGCCCCAGCCCCGCCUCUCUCGGCGGACCGCGCCCCCUUCCGGGAGCCCCGCCCCGUUCGCCGCGCCUCCUCCUCCGCACAGCUCCGGUUGCGGGGAGGCCCGGGUGGGUACCCGGCGCUCCGGCUCCCAGUCUCCUGGGCUUCUCCAGUCCUUCAGCGCCGUUCUCCGGUCACAGGGAAUGAAAGCGAGGAAGAAGGAAACGGUGUCGAGAAUUGCGAAGAGAGAAAGCAUAGAAAACCCACAUUAGAGGCACUCCCAGAGCAGAAACCCUUCGGAGCAUCCCGACUUCCUCGGCCCGCGUGCAAUCCAGGCAAAAUUGAGGUUGUCUCUGAGCCGCCCUCCCUAAGCAGGUCGGAAAGCCCCCGAAUCAUCCCAGGUCCCGCCGCGCUGCACUCGCAACCUGGGGUGGAGGUCCCUCUAGUGGUUGGCACCAAACAAAAGUUCUGUCUUAUGAAGAGCCGAGGUCAGGAAGCAUUUCCCUGUGCCCAGCGCCAAGGUCUGGGACCUUAGGUCCAAGAAAAGCGUUGGCAAUGUCUGACCACAGGAAUGGGUUCUCGAACUGGGGAGGACUGAAGCUGGAGAUCUGGUCCAGCCCCUACCUCCAGCGUGUGGCCUGAACCCGUUUUGGUUGUACUGCUAUGUUGUGGCCCUGCCCAGGCCUCCAAGGACUGGCUGCUGUUAAGCUGUUUAAAAUCCCUGUAGGCCUCAGAUGGCAGCGACACCAGGGACUCGGCAUAGUCCCCAGCUCUGGCAGGAGUCACCACAGCCCUAGCCUUUAGUUCUCUACAGGCUGGAGUGUCGACAAACUCCACAGGACACAACUUUUUCAAACCAAAUUUACCCUCGCGGUCUGAAAUGACCAGUAGGCCCAGGAGAAUUUUACAUGUGAACAGAACCUAACCCACCCUGGCAAAUAUGAGACGUGUGGUCACUGCGGGAACCUGGCCAGCAGCAGACCAAAGCACAGCCAGCAGGGGAAGGCUGGGGCCCGCAAGAGUUGUGUUACAACAGGACACCCUUCAGUUCUCUUUCACUUCCUUAAAAUAGCAGCAGAGCGACUUUUGUAGACGCAGGCUGCCACAGUUCACACAAGGUCAUGGCUGUUUCCGAAUCCCACCCUUUAUUGCCCUAGCGGAGCCACUCCCCUUACCUCCGCCCCCAGAAACUGCUAGCCUGUUCUUAAAUUGAUACAGUUACCUUUUUAAAUGUUCUAAGUCACCGGCUCUGGAGCUUCUUUGCACUUUGGAACCAACUUGCGGGAAGGAACUUUAAAAAUACUGAUAUCUCGAUCCAUCCCCAGAGGUUCUGAUUUAAUGGUCUUGGGGAUAUGGCCACGGCAUGAGGACUGUUAAAACUCCGCAGGUGAUUCUUAUGUGCAACAAAGUUUAAGAACCACUGAUGUAGGCCAUGUCGAUGUCAGUCUUCACUUAAAUCCAACAAGACCCCAGAGCUAAAACGUUCACCUGAAAGAAACCCCAUUCCCAGGCCUGCAUACUGACCUGCGCUGGCUCACAAGAAGCAAAGUGGUCCCUUAACAGGGGCUUCCUGGAGAAAAUGUCUUGACCUAAAAGAGUGAUUCGAGCUGCAGGGAUUUAAGCCUACUCAUUGUGAAGAGGAUGAUGCGGAUGAAGACCUUUAUGAUGAUCCACUUCCACUUAAUGAACCGUAUAUCUAUUUUCUUUUCCUUAUGAUUUUCUUAAUGACAUUUUCUUUUCCUAGCUUACUUUAUUUUAAGAACAAAGCCACAGGGCUCUUUCUUCCA